AUACUUGCUGGUCUGAUCCAUGCACAAGGCGGGGCUGCUAGGCCUCUGUGCCCGGGCUUGGAAUUCGGUGCGGAUGGCCAGCUCCGGGAUGACCCGCCGGGACCCGCUCGCAAAUAAGGUGGCCCUGGUAACGGCCUCCACCGACGGGAUCGGCUUCGCCAUCGCCCGGCGUUUGGCCCAGGACGGGGCCCAUGUGGUCGUCAGCAGCCGGAAGCAGCAGAAUGUGGACCAGGCGGUGGCCACGCUGCAGGGGGAGGGGCUGAGCGUGACGGGCACCGUGUGCCAUGUGGGGAAGGCGGAGGACCGGGAGCGGCUGGUGGCCACGGCUGUGAAGCUUCAUGGAGGUAUCGAUAUCCUAGUCUCCAAUGCUGCUGUCAACCCUUUCUUUGGAAGCAUAAUGGAUGUCACUGAGGAGGUGUGGGACAAGACUCUGGACAUUAAUGUGAAGGCCCCAGCCCUGAUGACAAAGGCAGUGGUGCCAGAAAUGGAGAAACGAGGAGGCGGCUCAGUGGUGAUCGUGUCUUCCAUAGCAGCCUUCAGUCCAUCUCCUGGCUUCAGUCCUUACAAUGUCAGUAAAACAGCCUUGCUGGGCCUGACCAAGACCCUGGCCAUAGAGCUGGCCCCAAGGAACAUUAGGGUGAACUGCCUAGCACCUGGACUUAUCAAGACUAGCUUCAGCAGGAUGCUCUGGAUGGACAAGGAAAAAGAGGAAAGCAUGAAAGAAACCCUGCGGAUAAGAAGGUUAGGCGAGCCAGAGGAUUGUGCUGGCAUCGUGUCUUUCCUGUGCUCUGAAGAUGCCAGCUACAUCACUGGGGAAACAGUGGUGGUGGGUGGAGGAACCCCGUCCCGCCUCUGAGGACCGGGAGACAGCCCACAGGCCAGAGUUGGGCUCUAGCUCCUGGUGCUGUUCCCGCAUUCACCCACUGGCCUUUCCCACCUCUGCUCACCUUACUGUUCACCUCAUCAAAUCAGUUCUGCCCUGUGAAAAGAUCCAGCCUUCCCUGCCGUCAAGGUGGCGUCUUACUCGGGAUUUCUGCUGUUGUUGUGGCCUUGGGUAAAGGCCUCCCCUGAGAACACAGGACAGGCCUGCUGACAAGGCUGAGUCUACCUUGGCAAAGACCAAGAUAUUUUUUCCCGGGCCACUGGGGAAUCUGAGGGGUGAUGGGAGAGAAGGAACCUGGAGUGGAAGGAGCAGAGUUGCAAAUUAACAACUUGCAAAUGAGGUGCAAAUAAAAUGCAGAUGAUUGCGCGGCUUUGAAUCCAA